GUUACGCGAUUUUCGCUCCCGCGGGCAGCGCCUCUCAGGCCACUCCCGAGGGACCCCGAGGACGCACUCGGGCCCCAGGGCGACGGUUCAAACGGGCCAUUGUGCGCCCCCGGGGUCCCCCGGCCCCUGCAGGGCUACUUGGGCGCAGAGCCGCGGAGGGUCUCCGUUCCUAGAGGUCCUCCUAUCCCGGGCUGCCUGAGUCCUCGCCAGCAUCCGCCCUCUCCCACUCCCAUCCUUCCUGGAUCCGCCUCUCGGUUCCCGAGGGACAGUCCCGACCGCAAACCCACGUAGAGUAAGGAAUGUGGGACAGGCGACAGAAGUGGCAUACGGUCCUGCGUUAUCCCUCCGUCUCGCCACACCUUGUGUCUCCAUCUCUCCCCACUUCCUUCCCUCCGUCUGUCAUCUGUCAUCCCCGGUCGCUCUAAGACCAGGAUUCCAAUUCGCCUAGUGAGGAAUCUCACUAGGGGAAUUUAUCGCGACAUCAUAAAUUAACGGGUUCAUUUUGACUGAAAAAGCGAAGGACUUUUUUCAGGCAGAAAACAAGUCUCGUCUGGACGGAUGUGAUCUUCGUGGUGGAAAGCUAAAUUUUAAAACCACCCCAAUGGAUGCAGACAGUGAUGUUGCAUUGGACAUUCUAAUUACAAAUGUAGUCUGUGUUUUUAGAACAAGAUGUCAUUUAAACUUAAGGAAGAUUGCUUUGGAAGGAGCAAAUGUAAUUUAUAAACGUGAUGUUGGAAAAGUAUUAAUGAAGCUUAGAAAACCUAGAAUUACAGCUACAAUUUGGUCCUCAGGAAAAAUUAUUUGCACUGGAGCAACAAGUGAAGAAGAAGCUAAAUUUGGUGCCAGACGCUUAGCCCGUAGUCUGCAGAAACUAGGUUUUCAGGUAAUAUUUACAGAUUUUAAGGUUGUUAACGUUCUGGCAGUGUGUAACAUGCCAUUUGAAAUCCGUUUGCCAGAAUUCACAAAGAACAAUAGACCUCAUGCCAGUUACGAACCUGAACUUCAUCCUGCUGUGUGCUAUCGGAUAAAAUCUCUAAGAGCUACAUUACAGAUUUUUUCAACAGGAAGUAUCACAGUAACAGGGCCCAAUGUAAAGGCUGUUGCUACUGCUGUGGAACAGAUUUACCCAUUUGUGUUUGAAAGCAGGAAAGAAAUUUUAUAAUUCACCACUUAAUUGGUUAGAAUCUCUAACUGAGCACCUUUUAAACCUGCUGCACAUUGGACUCAAAAGGAAAACUGGACCAACAAUAAUUGAGGAAAUAGACUCUUUUAUUCAUUCACGGCUACAGUGUAAGCUCCAGUCCCUUUGGAUUUUAUUCCAAACCUUGCUGUAAUAUAAAAGGAAGUUUACAAGACAUGAUAUUGCUGCUUUUACAAAAGGACAUUCUAUUUAUUUUCGCAGUAAUUCUCAUGUCCCCAUAAGCAGAGCUGUCACAGUGUGCACUACCUUAGAUUGUUUUAUUGUCGUCAUUGUUAUUUUUUUCCAUUUUGAGCUAAUGUGUUUUAUUUGUGAAUAGUCUUUUACAUUUUUGUAUGCUGAAUAUGGGCACCAAAGAACCUGUAAAAGUUAUCUUUUUCAAUUGAAUGUGCACAAAUAAAAGUUUGGAAAAGAUCUCUCUUCAUUCUAUAACUUUUAUUCCCCAUUUUCUAUUUUAACAAAAAUUGUAUUCAUACUUCUUUUUUUUAAAAUCUAUGCAAGCUUAAGACUUUGGCUAAAGUGUGUUGGCUUCUUUUUGAAGUGUAUUUUGUGUGUGUGUGUGUGUGUGUGUGUAUAUAUAUAUAUAUAUAUGCACCACAUGUGUAUAGUAUCUUUUAAUGCUCUGUUACCAAAUAACAAAUAGGAAUUUUUUUUCUUGCAGAUUAGAAAUAAAAACGUGUAUAUAAACUCUAGGGAACCAGACUAGAAGUUUAUAGAUAAAGGAUAAUGUUUUAUGUUGCUAAUUUAAUAUGAUAGAAAAUGUUAAAUAACUUGUAAAGGUUAAGAAAUUGUAGUUUUAAGAAGAGAAACCUCUUACCCACUAGAUGGAAAUGAGAAAGAAGCUGUGAUGAAUGGUGCCUCAUUUGGACCUUUGUUUUUCUGGAAAGACUCAACACCUGUAGUUGUAGAGAAGUGAUUGAGGUUCUUGACUUUAAUCUUGGGUUGAUGCCCAAGCCUAUACUAAGAGUCUUGUCAGAAGUUGGUAACAUGGAGAUGUUUUAACAAGAAGUGCCCAUAAGCUGCCUCUGUGCCACAGUGUAAUUAUCAAAUAGCCCCACUUGAAUUUGAAAGCCAUUUUGUGUGAUACUGUCCUUCCCCUUGCUGUAUCUUAUUUAAUGGAGUUAAAGAGUGACUAUUCAGUAUAUGAGAUUGCUACUCUUAAAGUUAUAAUAAAUAUGCAUUUAUGAAACAGUGUCUCUGGCUCACCCAGGAGCCCUGAUGUGGUAAUACAGGAUCAAGCUGUAGUUGUGCCCUGUCAUUUAGGUUUAGGAGUUUAGUGUAACCAACAGUGAUUAUACCUAGAAAUAAAGCUGAGUGGAGAGUCCAAUUAGCUUCUCAGGAGAAACUUAAUGGGGACAAUAUUCCAACACAAUGUUCCACAAAAACUUGUAUUUCCAAAAUGUUUUUAAACCUUUGUGGAAAAAUUGCAACAUCCUAAUCUCCAUAUAUAGUACAUUUUCCUUACUGUAUUAUAAAAUCUUGAAAACCUAGCUUAGGCACUGCACUGAACAACACAUAUUAUUUUUAUCUUUUUUCUUCUCAAUGCCUUCCCUAACCUCCUGCUUAUUCCAAAGUGGAAAGCAAAGGCUAACUUACAUUUUUCCUUCUUGUGAAAUAUUUCAUUGAGAUUUUUAGACUUGUAUUUUUCCUUUUUUUUAAAAAAAAAGUGUUUAUUUCCUUUAUUUUAAGAUUCAGUAGGAUAGCCAAAUUCAUAGAGAAUAAAAUUACAUGAAAGAGUUACAAGCUCACUGUUUUAAAGACUUGACAUUUUUCAUUUAGUUUUAAUUAACAGUAAUAAGUCACCUCCUGUUUUUCAAUGUUCACCAAAAAAAGAAACAUAGAAUAGGGGGAAAACAUGCUUAUAUAGCCAAGGUACAGAUCCAGAUGAUGUAACCUUUUUAGUAUUCGCAUGACUUGAAAACUGGGCAGAUCAAUAGAUAAUCGAAGUGCUUUAUCUGAAGGGAGAGGGUAAAGACAGUGUGACCAGGUUUGUUUUCAGGGCUGCCGAAUGAGCCUCACCUAACAGUGUCCAUGGGUAAUUCGCUAACCUUAACAAAGAUGGGAAGAAGUGAGUGCUCUGAUGUCUUCUGCUGGCUCUCCAUAAGUACUGUAAAUUUUUUUUAUAAAUAAAAACUGUGAAUAUAUAUGUACAAGUUGUAAGUAUUUCCCCCUUUUUAUUUUUGAAAAUCAAGAAGCUUGAUUUGGUGUGGUGCAAUGGAUAUUGGAUAAAAAUUUGAAGACAAAAUUGUUUAGUUACAGACUCAGGAUAAUAAAAGAAAAAUAUAAAAGAAUGCUCAAGAUACUGAAGUCAAGGUCACUAGUAAUAAACUGGCUAGGUUGAUAAACAAUUUCCUGCCCAUUUAUAAUGAAGGGCUAAACAAAAAAUACCUGAAGUAUAUAUAGAGUUUGAACUAUAAACACGGAAGGAAACAUGGGGCAGAACACACUUCCCUUCUCUUUCCAAAAACAAAAAACAAUGCAUGCUCUGAUUUGCGUAUGAAAUACACCAUGAUAGAAUUGAGAUCUCCAAUCUCCUUUCCUUUUAGCUUCCCCCUGCCAAUUUUUAUACAGAUAAUACACUGCAGAUCCAGGCCUUUUAGUCAGUCUCCUGAGUCUCUGAUAUAGUUUUACUACUUACAUAGGUUUAUAGUCUCUCCACAUUGUUAUAAAGGAAUGUAAUAGAUCAUGUUUCCUUAUAUGACAUUGGGACAGUUUGUUAGGAACCAAUAGGAAAAUUCCAAGCUAAAUAAAAAGGAGCUUUGGCUCUUAGGAUUCUCUUUUCUUCAGGUUAAUCAUAUUUUAAAAUUCUUUUUCAAGUUAGGUUGUUCGUGCUUUUAAGUUUUUUGUGUGUCUUCCAUCACUUAAAUAUUAGUAAUUUAAUAUGUUAUUUGGUUCAAGAUUUGAUUGUGGAUUUUCUAUCAUACCCAAAUUUUAUUAGUAAGACCUCUUAACAAGUCUUUAAAAUCAACUGGAGAAGUAAGAGAACAGUUCAUCGUUGUGUGGGUGAAACCCACGUUGCUGGUACAGGUGGCCAUCAUAGAAAAGAACAUGAGGGAAUUGUCCUGAUGUCUGAAUGUCAUUUAUUGUGUCUUCAGUUAUCUGAACAUCAUCAUCAAUUAUAGCCUGUGUACCGUAACCUGAGGUAGUGAUAUUCCUGAGGAGUGUGAAGAAUUGGACACUGUGGAUUACUAUACAUUGUCAUGAAAGCCUUACAAGGAGGCAGCUUUUCUAGGCUUGACUUAAUAACUUCAACCUAAUUGCUUAGAGAUUUGGAUAAAUAACCUAAUGGCCUGACUCCUUUUCUAAUGUUUUACUAACAGCUACUUCUAAAUAAAUAUGGUCCCAGGAUUUUAAAA